CUUCUGCCGCGGGCGGCUGGCCCAGCUGGAGGAAGCGGCGGCGGCGGCCACGAUGAGUGCGGGCGACGCAGUGUGCACCGGCUGGCUCGUUAAGUCGCCCCCCGAGAGGAAGCUACAGCGCUACGCCUGGCGCAAGCGCUGGUUUGUCCUCCGGCGAGGCCGCAUGAGCGGCAACCCCGAUGUCUUGGAGUACUACAGGAACAAGCACUCCAGCAAGCCCAUCCGGGUGAUAGACCUCAGCGAGUGUGCAGUGUGGAAGCAUGUGGGCCCCAGCUUUGUUCGGAAGGAAUUUCAGAAUAAUUUCGUGUUCAUUGUCAAGACUACUUCCCGUACAUUCUACCUGGUGGCCAAAACUGAGCAAGAAAUGCAGGUGUGGGUGCACAGCAUCAGUCAGGUCUGCAACCUUGGCCACCUGGAGGAUGGUGCAGCAGAUUCCAUGGAGAGCCUCUCUUACACGCCCUCCUCCCUGCAGCCAUCCUCUGCCAGCUCCCUUCUUACCGCCCAUGCUGCCAGCUCCUCUUUGCCAAGAGAUGACCCAAACACUAAUGCCGUAGCCACUGAGGAAACCAGAAGUGAGUCAGAGCUUCUCUUCCUUCCAGAUUAUCUGGUUUUGUCCAACUGCGAGACUGGAAGACUGCACCAUACCAGUCUACCCACCAGAUGUGAUAGCUGGUCAAACUCAGACCGUUCAUUGGAACAGGCUUCAUUUGAUGAUGUUUUUGUUGACUGCCUGCAGCCGCUCCCCUCCAGUCAUUUGGUCCACCCCUCAUGCCAUGGCAGUGGAGCUCAGGAGGUGCCAUCCUCGAGGCCUCAGGCUGCCCUGAUCUGGAGUAGAGAAAUCAAUGGGCCACCCAGGGACCACUUGUCUUCUUCACCAUUGCUGGAAAGUUCCUUAAGUUCCACCAUUCAGGUAGAUAAAAAUCAAGGUUCCUUACCCUGUGGAGCAAAAGAACUAGACAUUAUGUCCAACACUCCACCUCCCCGCCCCCCUAAGCCAAGCCAUCUGUCUGAACGGCGCCAAGAGGAGUGGAGUACACACAGUGGUAGCAAGAAGCCAGAAUGCACUCUGGUUCCAAGAAGAAUCUCCCUCUCUGGUUUAGACAACAUGAGAACCUGGAAAGCUGAUGUAGAAGGCCAAUCCUUAAGACACCGAGACAAGCGGCUUAGUUUGAAUUUGCCAUGCAGGUUCUCCCCGAUGUACCCCACAGCUUCAGCCAGUAUCGAAGACAGCUAUGUGCCCAUGAGCCCCCAGGCUGGUGCCUCUGGUCUUGGACCCCACUGCAGCCCUGAUGACUACAUUCCAAUGAACUCAGGAAGCAUCUCAAGCCCGUUGCCUGAGCUGCCUGCAAACCUGGAACCUCCCCCAGUGAAUAGAGAUCUCAAGCCUCAGAGGAAAUCACGGCCACCUCCUCUGGACCUGAGAAACCUCUCGAUCAUCCGGGAACAUGCAUCUCUUACCAGGACCCGCACUGUGCCUUGCAGUCGAACCAGCUUUCUCUCUCCAGAAAGAAAUGGUAUUAAUUCUGCAAGAUUUUUUGCUAAUCCUGUUUCCAGAGAAGACGAAGAAAGCUACAUCGAAAUGGAGGAGCACCGAACAGCCAGUUCCCUGAGCAGUGGUGCCCUUACGUGGACAAAGAAAUUCAGCCUAGAUUAUUUGGCCCUGGACUUCAAUUCAGCAUCACCAGCCCCCAUGCAGCAGAAACUUCUCCUUUCAGAAGAACAAAGAGUAGACUAUGUCCAAGUGGAUGAGCAGAAGACACAGGCUCUCCAGAGCACAAAACAGGAGUGGACGGAUGAAAGGCAAUCCAAAGUAUGAGAGGUGCGGGCUUGUGCCAUGUGUGAAACAGGGAAGCUUGGGGCUCAGUUUGAGUUUUUUCUUUUUUUUUUUUUUUUGUCCACUAAAAACACACUGAUGGUCAACACAGGUCAAAACCAAGAGAGAAUGUGUAGUUUUCAAGGUCUUGGCCAGAACCUUUAGGAAAGAAGACCUGUUUAUACAUUGAAGGAAGAAAAGAAGGAAGCAGUUGCCUUCCGGAGGGGGCUCUGAGAGAAUCUAGCCUCCCCUCUGUCCUAUUGGAGCAAAGAUUGGAGUGAGUGUUGCCACCAACAGGAUUUUAUCGUUUGACUCCAAUACCUGAAAUUCUGACUUCUCUCCUGUGCUUCAAUGAGAAUGAUAAAUUAUCCUAGCAAAGGGGCCUCUGGAGACCAUCUUGUUCCAGCCUCUGAAGACAGUUGAGGAGAUCAAGCCCAGCAAUGGUGGCAGAAUCUUACUCCACAGACUUCAGCAGACUAGUCAUUUCAAUACCCAAAGAAAGACAAGUGACAGGGGCAAUGGAUCUCAGGCUCUGAGAUAAGUAUAUCAGAUGACACUGGUGGCUCUAAGGAUAUUGCAAUUAAGCAGCUACCUGUAGCCAGGUAUUCUGCUGCUCUUGGCCUUUUCCCACGCAUCGUCUCGUGUCUUCUCCGAAAGACCUUGGAAGAUAGGCCUGGAAGAGACUGUUGAUGCCACUUUGAAGAAAAGAACACUGAGAACUAGAGGAGGGAACACUUUGCCCAAGAUUACUCACAAAGCCAAGACCCAGAGUCCAGCUUAGAGAAUAGAGUUGUUCAGGCUGCCAAUUGCAAGCUCAUUCCUCUACCUCAUACUUCCUCUGAGGAUUUUGACAAAAUGGAUUAAUUGGGUGAGCCUUGGAGACAUGUGGGAAACACCUGCAGACACAAAAUGAGUAGUCAUCCUGUCUCCCUUUCAAUAGGGAUCUGAACAGGUGUUUUGAUACUUGAAAGAUGUGCAUGUCAAGUGAGGGUUUCUUUCUGCGAUGUUCAACUGGAACUCUCCCAUCAGUAGUUACAAUUAGAAAUACCUACUGAUGGUUAGUCUGAAGGCCAUUCUCAUGGUCACCUAUACAGUGUGUUUCCCUGUGAGCUAGCAGACACAAUGACCAGGAAAAAACCUAUGAAUUCCAUUCUUAGGUUUCCCAGCCAAUUGCUCCCUUCUGCUUUAGAAGUGACUAGGUACUGAGAGUACAAACACUCCCACUUUAUAAUGAAGGCGUCAUGUCACCCCUUCCUUUACAGGUCCUGGGGUCCAGGAGACCCAGAAUGAAGGUGUCAGUUGGGCAUGAAGUGUUAUUUAGUGUCCAUUCUUGAUCCUUCUGAGCACCUACAGCUGGAAACUAAGCAGAUACUGGUCCUGCAUUCUGACUGAGAUUGUGUCUUCUUUAUGAGGAUAGAUCAAAUUGGCAGUCAGGCCCAUGAUAGUCAGUGCAGUUGGGGCAGUUGUAGACUUUGCUACAGGAUUUCAGGGUUUCCAAUCACCCCACAGGUAAGUGAAUGCCAAAGUCUUCUUUUUUCAGACCAUACAAGAAGUCAUUUUGAUUUUCAAAGAAGCCGUUUUGAUUUUCAAAGAAGCAGGUUCUGGUGACAUUAUUUUCUUCCUUGGACAAAGUGGGGGGAAAUUUCUAAGUAUUUUAACUGAGUUCAGGGUCCUUAGUGAGCCUGGACAGAGCAAGGAGAGGGCUCCCCACUCCCUAAGCCCCACAGCCAGCUCUGCAUCACCACACACAGCCAGAGCCUGUGAGGAGCUGCCUUCUUCCCCAUGUGACUUGCAAAGAGUCUCAGGCAAGAAACCAGGGCUUCAAACUGCUAGUUCCCAUGGAGGGUAGUUCCCUCGUGUGGAGCACUUGUGUUAGGAUCACUGAUUAUCUGACAAAGGCUGGUGCAGAAAAAAAAUUGUAGGCCCAAGUGUCAAGAACCACACCAGAUUGGAGAUAGAAAAGAAUAGCUGAAAUUAUGUCAGUAGUGAAAUGUCACUCCAUUGACCCACCGAAAAAAGAAAAGAAAUCUGUUUCUACCAAACAUUUCCAGAAACGUAUUUAUAGCAUGAAGAAACACACAUGGGUAGUGUGACCUGUUUGGAUGUGAUUACUUAAAAAUGGAAUGCUCUGAAUAGGCACUCUCUACAUUAAAGGUAUGGAAGGCGAUAGGGGUCAGAAUUUUAAAAAUUUAAUUUUGAAAAAGGUGACUCACCCCUCAUUUCCAGAGUGUAGGCAAUUAUGUCCUGCUUUGAUAAAACUGCUAGAGGAUGGCUAUGCAAAAGCAUAACGAUUCAAGGAAACAAAGUACAGGUAGUUUUUGAGCUGACAGCAGCAAAGGCACCAUAAGUCAAAAUAUUGGUUUUGGUGGAGAUGAUCGAUGUGUGUGUGUGAGAGAGAGCUAUGUUUCUAACCAAGGGCCUAAUGUUUGUUACAGAAAUGAUCCCAGAGACCUACAAGAUGUGGGAAUCAGCAUAACAGGGCAAUGCAGCAAUUAACCCCACAUCGUUUUCUGUAGUUCCUUUUUGUUUCAUUUUCUUCUGUCUCACCUCGUUAGAAAAUUCCUCCCAGUCAGGGGUCGUCCAGUGCAGGACGGGGGACCCAAGGGUCUCAAGCCUGCAAGUCCAGAAGGUGACAAACCCAGGAGCACUGGGAGUUAAGCUUUCCUUGGGGAGGGAAGAGCCUUGAUGUCCAGCACACAGCCUGGCUAUAAAGACACGAAGCGACCUACCCACUGUACAGUCCACUUCACAGGAUCAGCUGAAUCAUGACCUUUAAAAGUUCCGAGUUGAAACUGAAGGCUCUCCUCAGACCUGGCUUUUUCCUCAGUCCCUGUUCAUACCAUCUCUGCACCCACAAUCACACUGAUUUUUCAAAUUCAUUUUGUUUUUGCUGUUUCAUUUCUGGCAUUAAUAAAAGUCUUAUAAGGAGAAA